CCAGCCACAGUGAUCAAGAAAAGCGCGAAGGCCGGGCCGAACGCGACGAAAGUGCAGCCGAAAAACACCGCAGCCCCCAUGGCUGGUCAGCUCCAGACAGACAGAAGAAAGGGAUUCUUUUCAGUCUAGAAAAAUGCUCACCCCUUCCUCAGAACAUUUCCACUGUGACGAAAAGAGACUGAUGAAGCCUCAGAGAGAAAGGCAACUCUGGGUGGUGAUGCAAUAGUGCAGAAUCCAGAAUGGAUGUCCUCUUUGUAGCCAUCUUUGCUGUGCCACUUAUCCUGGGACAAGAAUAUGAGGAUGAAGAAAGACUGGGAGAGGAUGAAUAUUAUCAGGUGGUCUAUUAUUAUACAGUCACCCCCAGUUAUGAUGACUUUAGUGCAGAUUUCACCAUUGAUUACUCCAUAUUUGAGUCAGAGGACAGGCUGAACAGGUUGGAUAAGGACAUAACAGAAGCAAUAGAGACUACCAUUAGUCUUGAAACAGCACGUGCAGACCAUCCGAAGCCUGUAACUGUGAAACCAGUAACAACGGAACCUCAGAGUCCAGAUCUGAACGAUGCCGUGUCCAGUUUGCGAAGUCCUAUUCCCCUCCUCCUGUCGUGUGCCUUUGUUCAGGUGGGGAUGUAUUUCAUGUAGAAGGUGGAAGAAGGCUGCUAUGACUCUUUGGAUGGGAGUCUGGCAAGAGGAAAUUGGAAGAUAAAAUAAAUAAUAAGUGAAAUAAUCUGGUUA